AGCCGCCCAGACCGGCGAGACCAGCCUGCGGGAGCAGCCCCAUGGCGGAGCAGCUGGCCCUGGUGAUUGGGGGCACCAUCGGGGGGCUGCUGCUGCUGCUGUUGAUCGGGGCAAGCUGCUGUCUGUGGAGAAGGUUCUGUGCCACCCUCACCUAUGAGGAGCUGCCUGGGACACCAGCCAUGGCCACCACAGCUGCCUCCAGUGGGCAGCGGGACAGGCCCUGCCAGCCGCAUGCUAGGACCCAACUGAGCAGGCCACCAGCUGUGCCAUUCGUGGUGCCCCCAACCCUUCAAGGCCGAGAUUGGGUGCCCCUGCACAGUGGAGAGUGGGCCGAUGCCCCAUGGGACCCCUGCCCGGCAUCAGAGCUGCUGCCUCACACCUCCAGCGGCGGCCUUGCCCUCCCACCCUCUGUCAUAGGAGAUGCAUGUAUGGUGGGGGCCAUCAACCCAGAGCUGUACAAGUUCCCGGAGGACAAAAGUGAGACCGACUUCCCCGACGGCUGCCUGGGGCGGCUGUGGUUCUCGGUGGAAUAUGAGCAGGAGGCUGAGCGGCUGCUGGUGGGCUUGAUCAAGGCACAGCACCUGCAAGCCCCCUCGGAGACCUGCAGCCCCCUGGUGAAGCUCUACCUGCUGCCCGAUGAGCGGCGCUUCCUCCAAUCCAAGACCAAACGCAAAACCUCCAACCCGCAGUUUGACGAGCACUUCAUCUUUCAGGUGUCCAGCAAGACCAUCACCCAGAGGGUGCUGAAGUUCUCCGUCUACCACGUGGACAGGCAGAGGAAGCACCAGCUCCUGGGCCAGGUGCUCUUCCCCUUGAAGAAUGAGACCCUAGUGGGGGACUGCCGGCGUGUCAUCUGGAGAGACCUGGAGGCCGAGAGCCUGGAGCCCCCCUCGGAGUUUGGCGACCUCCAGUUCUGCCUCAGCUACAACGACUACCUGAGCCGCCUGACGGUGGUUGUGCUGCGUGCCAAGGGCCUCCGGCUCCAGGAGGACAGAGGCAUUGUCAGUGUGUUUGUCAAAGUGUCUCUGAUGAACCACAACAAGUUUGUCAAGUGCAAGAAGACUUCAGCUGUGCUGGGCUCCAUCAACCCUGUGUACAAUGAGACCUUCAGCUUCAAGGCCGAUGCCACCGAGCUGGAUACCGCUAGCCUCAGCCUGACUGUGGUGCAGAACAUGGAAGGGGACAAGCAGGCUACUACAGUGGAACUGUUUCUGUUUCAUCUGACAUCCGGAUAGAUGCCAGCCACCCCCACAUUCCAAGGUGAGAUUUCUGACUAGCAGUGACUUUUCUAGGGCCGCUUGGAAAAGUUGAUAAGUAUCCUUUUCUGCAGGACAGAGUAGACUGGUAUCUCUGACUCAUCCCUGAAAAAUCUAAAUGGCAAGAGACUAGCUGGCUCUCUGCUCUGAUGGGGAGGAGGUUGUUGUUUGGGCUGUUCUCUACAGACAUAGUCAGGGCAAAAAGCAUACGCAUGCUUCCCAUGGACCAGAGAAACCUGGCCUGGGUUGUCUCAAAUCCUGUCCACAAGGCAACUCCAGAAGAAAGAAGCCCUUUACAUUUCCAUAAAACACUUUAGAAUCAGCUAGUCAAUUUCCACAAAAUAAAGUGCUAGAAUUUGAUUGGAUUUAAUUGAUUAUGUAGAACAAUUUGGGGGCCAUUUGACAUCAUUAAAAUAUUCAAUCUUCCUAUUCAUUAACAUGGUAUAUCUCUUCACUUUAAGUCUUUUGUAUGUUUCUCAGAACUAUUUUUGUGGUUUUCAGUAAAGUGUUCUUGCACAUCCUUCAAUAGAUUUAUUCUUAGACGUUUUAUAUUUGUUUAUGGCUAGUAUAUACAGAUUCUGUUGCUACAAAACUAUGUUGACCUUGUUAUCCAGUGAGAGGCUUUGUGACAUUCAUUUAAAUUGUAAUAAUUUGCAGAUUAUUUUUGUAUAAUCAUGUCCUCUGUGAAUGACAGUUUUAUUUCUUCCUUUCUUAAUCUUUAUGCCUUAUUUAGCUCUUGCCAAACUGCAGUGGCUGAGCAAUUGGACAAGAUAAAGAAAUAAAAGUGAUCCAGAUCAUAAAGAAAGAAGUAAAACUAUAUCUGCACAUGACAUAAUCUUGUCUAUGGAAAAUCCUAAGGAAUCCACACACAAAAAAACUACUAGAGCUAAUAAGUUUGGCAAGGUUGCAAGAUAUAAAAUUGGUAUACAAAUUGCAGUGGCUAGGACCUCCAGCAGAAUGCUGACUAUAAGUAGUGAUAGUGGGUAUUCUUGUCUCAUCCUCAAUCUCAGGGGUGGUGGGUGUGGCAUGUGGAGAGUUGUCAAUAUUCACCAUGAAGUUUGAUGGUUGUUAUAGGAUUUUUAAUGUACUCAUUAACAUAUAUUCUCAAGCUGUUAAAAAGAUUUUUUUAAUUACAAAUAAGGUUAAAUUUCUCUCAAAUACUUACUCUGCACCUUUUGAAAUAAUUUUAUUUUUCUCCUUUAUUCUUUGGAUGUGAUGACUUAUACUAAUUGACUGUUGAAUGUCAAACCAAACUUAACAUUCUUGUAAUAGAAACCAGCAGGGUGUGUACACUUUUGUGUGUGUGCGCAGGUUUAUACACAUAAACACAACAAUACUUGGACUUAUUUAUUUAAAAUUUAGAUUUAUUAGAGGGAGCAUGGCCAUAAAAUAAAAUAAAAUAAAAUUUAGAUUUAAGUCGAGCUCAGUGGCUCACAUCUAUUAUCCCCGCACUUUGGAAGGCCAAGGCAGGUAGAUUGUCUAAGCUCAGGAAUUUGAGACCAACGUGGUGAAACUCGGUCUCUACAAAAACCACAAAAAUUAGCCAGGUAUGGUGUCACAUGCCUGUUGUCCCAGCUACUUGGAGGGCUGGGGCAGGAGUAUUGCGUGAGCCCGGGAGGUUAAGGCUGAAGUGAGUCAUGUUCACGCCACUGCACUACAGCUUGGAUAACAAAGCGAGACUCUGUCUCCAAAAAUAAAAUAAGUAAAUAAAUAAAUAAAUAAAAUUUAGAUCAAUUUGCUGUUAUAUUUUUAUAUAAACUAUGUUUAUGACAUAAGUAUAAACAAAAAAAUAAAAUAAGUAAAUAAAUAAAUAAAAUUUAGAUUAAUUUGCUGUUAUAUUUUUAUAUAAGCUAUGUUUAUGACAGACUUUCCUAUAAUAUUCUUAUCAUAAUGUUCUUGCACUUGAAAGAAUGUGCAUUCUGCAGUUGUGUGCAGGUGUUAUGUGUAUUUCAACUGGGUCAAGUUUGUUAAUCAGGUUGGUCAAAUUAUCUACAUCUUUACUGAUAUUUUUGUCUGUUUUUCUAUAAAUUACUGAGAGAGGAUAAAGCCUGCCACUGUUAUUAUGAAUUUGUUUAUUUCUCCUUUGAGUUUUGUUAGUUUUUGUUUUAUGCAUUUAGAGGUUGUGUUAUUAGGCUCAUACCCAUUUAAAAUUGACGUUUUCUGGUAGAGUGAACCUUUAUUAUGUGAAAUGGCUUUCUCUACCACUCACAAUGGUAUUUUUUUCACUUUCCCCCUUAUUUUUGAAUUUUCAAUGUUCUUAUAAUGAUGUCAUGUCUCUUGAAUAGAGUUGUUUUAAUCAAGUCUGUCAAAUUUUGUCUUUUGUGUAUUUCGUGAAUUUACAUUUAUUGUAAUUACUGAUAUAGUUGUGUUCAUAAAUACCAUCUUACUACUUGUUUCCAUUUGUCUUACCCAUUUUUGUUUUUAUUUUUUCUUUUCUGUUGCUUUCUUUCUGAUUAUUUUUUUAAUUCCGUUUCCCCCCCUACCAUUGGUUCUACUUACACAUUCUUUUAUAAUUUCUUUAGUGGUUUCCUCCACAGAUUACAACUUCUGUACAUUAUUAUAAUCUAAUACAAAUUUUACUUUUUAUUGUUUCCCAGACAAUGCUAUGAUCUCACAAUACUCAAUCUCUAUUUACCUCCAUUCUACUCUUGCAUGUAUAUUAUUAUUACUCAUUUUAAUUUCACAUAUAUUUUACACCUAACGAGACAUUAUUAUUAUUGCUAUGUGCAGUCAAUAUUCAUUUGUAUUCACCCACAUAUUCACUCUGUUUUUUUUUAUUAUUUCCUGCAUUUCUGUGAUUCUAUCAUAGAUCAGUUUUCUUCUACCUGAAGAAUUCCCUUUAGUAUUUUUUGUGUAUGCACAUCUGCUGGCAGCAAAUUUUCUCAGGUUUUUUUGUGUUUUUUUGUUUGCUUGUUUUUGAGACAGGGUCUCACUCUGUCGCCCAGGCUGGAGUGCAGUGGCAUGAUCAUGGUUCACUGUAGCCUCAACCUCCUAGGUUCAAGCAGUCCUCCCACCUCAGCCUCCCGAGUAGCGGGACUACAGGCAGGCACCACCAUACCUGGCUAAUUCUUUUGUAUUUUUUGUAGAGAAGGGAUUUCACCAUGUUGCUCAGGCUGGUCUCAAACUCCAGAGCUCAAACAGUCUGCCUGCUUUGACCUCCCAAAGGACUGGGAUUACAGGCCACCUCACCCAGCCUUUCUCAGUUUUUGAAUAGAAACAUCUAUUUCAAAUUCAUUUUUAAGUAUAUUUUGUGAAUAUAGGAUUACAGGUUGACACUUUUUUCUUUGAGGAACUUCAGAAUGGCACUCCAUUAUCUUCUCACUUCCAUCAUUUCUGUUGACAAGUGAUUUUCAGUGCUAUUGUUUCUCCUUUGAGAGUAAUGUGUCAGUAACAUGCACUGGCUCACGCCCGUCAUCCCAGCACCCUUGAGCCCAGGAGUUCAAAACCAGCCCAGGCAACAGAGCAAGAUCCCCCCCCUCUACAAAAGAAAAUGACAGGAGGGAGGCAGGAAGGAGGAGAGAGGGAGGGAGGGGAAAAGAAAAAAGAAAAGAAGAAAUGUGUCCCUCCUACCUGCCUCUAGCUGCUUUUACUGUUUUUUCCUUGUCUUUCAUUUGCAGCAGUUUAAGUAUAGUGUGCCUGGGUUGGGUGCGGUGGCUCACGCCUAUAAUCCCAGCAGUUUGGGAGGCCAAGGCCAGUGGAUCACCUGAGGUCAGAAGUUUGAGACCAACCUGGCCAACAUGGUGAAACCCCGUCUCCACUAAAAAAUCCAAAAAUUAGCCAGGCAUGGUGGCGCGUGCCUGUAAUCCCAGCUAUUCGGGAGACUGAGGCAGGAGAAUCGCUUGACCUUGGGGAGGCGGAGGUUGCAGUGAGCUGAGAUCGCGCGCCACCGUACUCCAGCCUGGGUGACAAAGAAAAACUCCGUCUCAAAAAAUAAUAAUAAAAAAAAAGUAUAGUGUGCCUGGAUGCAGUUUUGUUUUUAUUUAUCCUGCUUGGGGAUCAUAAAGCUUUAUCAGUUUUGGAAAGUUCUCAGGCUAUAUUUAUUUAACUGUUCCUUCUGCCCCAUCUUCCUCCCUUCUAAGACUCCAGUUACAUAUGUGUUAGGCCUGUUCACCACCUCCCACAAGUAUCUUAUGUUCUUUGCUGUAUUUUCCAUACUCUUUGUCUCUGUUCUUCAGCUUAGAGUUUUUAUUCUGUCCUAUAUUACAGUUCAAAGAAUGUUCCUUCUGCUAAAUCUAAUUGUAGUUAACCCAUAUGCUAAGUAGUUAAUUUCAAUUAUUGUAUUUUUAAGUUUUAAAUUUCCAUUUCAUUCUUUCUUAUAGAUUCCAGUUCUUUGAUGAAAGUCUCUAUUCCACCCAUCAAGUCUGUGUCUGAUAACACCAAUAUCUGGGUCAUUAGUGGCUCCGUUUUGUUGUGUCUGUUUUCCCCUCCUUCCUGUUUUGUGGUGUGUUUGAUCACUUAUUGUUGAAUGCUAACCAUUAUAAUAAAUUUUAGUGGCUCCAGGAAA